GCCCGCUUUGUCCCGGCCCGCGGGGCGGCGCGCUUUGUCCGGCCGCGUGCGGUCGGCGGGGUCGGGGUCGGGGUCGGGGUCGGGUCCCGGCGGCCGGGGUGAGCCGGGGCGGGAGCAGGCGGGGACGGGACGGAGAGGGUCCCGUGCCAGCCACACAGGACAUUGCAUGCUUGUGUGAGGUGCAGGUUUGCCCCGGUCUUAACCUGCUACAUGUCGUCUGCCCUCCCCCUCUCGGAGCAGCCACAGUUCCAACGCUGGAGAGCCCGGGGGUUUCAGCUCUGCCGUUCUCCUCCCGCAUAUCUGCGGUUCGCUGUGCUGUUUCUUUCAUUACCUGUGGUACCUACUCCAUCUUCAUCUUCCUCUCCCAUCGCCUGAGCUCCUGAGGGGAAGUGAUAUUUGAGUUUAGUGUGGGGUAGGGCCUGAGCAGACCUAGAAGCUAACCCUGGGUCACACUCACCCCUGAAACUUUGUGUCUUCUCAACACUCAUGGCUCCUCUAACCAAUUCCAGCUGCUUCUCAUCUUUGGACAAGGGUGGCCCUCAAAGUGUGGUCCCCAGACCAUUAGCUUCAGUGUCACCCGGGAACAGGUUAGAAAUGCACAUUCCCAGGUACCACCCCAGAAGUACUGAAUCGUAAACUGGGGGAUGGGGGGGUGACCUGUGAUUUAACAGUCCUCCAGGUUGUUGUGAUUCAUGGAAGUUUGAGAAUCCCCAGACCUGAGCUGUUGAGCUCAACCCUGAAAGUAUUCCAGCCCAGGAGCAGGUCUUCUCCAAUCCCGUGUUCAUUCUUUCCUUGAGCUUCUCUCUAGUCCUAAGAAAGACAUUAAUUCCAUGGCCAAAAAAAAUGAAUUAUAGUCAAGUCAUUCAAUAUCUCUUUAUUGAAUAUCUGUUGUACUGAGUCUGGAAAAACACCAAAACGAGUAAGACAGCCCUUGUCCUCAAUGAGUUAAAUGUGGAGCGGGCAGAGAGACACGUAAACAACUAACCGUAAUGCGAUGUGAUAAGUACAAUACUAGCUGCAUGCCGAAGUGCCCUGGAAGCACAGAGGAGGGAAUGAUCAACUCUGAGGGAGGGAAAUAAUUCAUCAGGAGCAGGAUGUGGUGAGAGGAAGAAUUAGGAUACAAGGCAGCCUGUAGCCCAGGGUAUAGGAUUUCUAGCUUAACAUGUCAGCUGAAAGAGAGGAAAACUGCCCUGGAGGAUCGGCACGGUGAGCCUAGUCUGCCUCCAGCAGCGCCUGGAGUACAUUCCAGCAGGACCCCAAGCCUGCAGCCGGCGGGGGUUGGCAUUCUUCUAGCACUAACAGUGUAAGCUACUUGGGCCUGGCCUUGAGGUCAAUUGCUAAGAAUAAGGUAUGAUGAGACUGUAAUCUGGAUUAGCUACUGCACCACCCUAUUGCCAGACUUCAGGAAUCUGUGGAAGAGAGGACGAUUGAGGAUUCUCCAGCUUCCUCAUGACAGGGGGUCAUGAAGCUGGGGGGCUGCUGGCCGACUGAGGAAAUGUGAGCAUGGAGACCCUGGUCAUAGGUGAGGAAUGAUCUACUCAGUGGCAAGAAACCAGCGCUGGAUAUGUGUAGGAGAAAAGCAAAUAGAAAUCAGUGGGAAUCUAGAGAUGGCAGCAGGGGACACAAGCUGAGAACACAGCAUAUUGUCCAAAAGGCCAGGGAGCUACAGAGCCAGAAUGCUUGGAAACCAAGACCUAGAGACACAAAGGUAGCAGAGCCUCAGAGCCACAUGCUGAACAAUGCCAGAGAGCACCAUUCACAUGGAAGGCUGUGGAGUUGCAACAUGGUGGCCCUGUGGGGGUCUGUGAUCUAAGGACACCAGUGCCAGCUUGGUUCCUGAUCCAUAUCACAGCAUUUCUGGAAACUCAGAACACACAGCAUGCAUGCUUCAAAUUCAAUUUGGAGAGAGGAGCAUUUAAGUGGCUGAGGUUUUAUUUGGGGGAAGAGGAGGUUCUAGCUCCAUACUUUCUCCUGGUAAUGGUAGGAAUCCGCAGAGACAUUCUAACAGUUGGACUUCCCUGGAGGGUCUGGCUCCCAGUUGGGCCCCUUUGUAACUUUAACAAAACCCCCAAUUCUGCAUUUCUCCUGAGCCCUACUUCCUACCACCAGGGCUGUGGUCUUGGCAGUCUCUGGUUCUGGAAAGGAAGGAGGUAUGGAGAAGAGAGAAGUGAUGGGUGGUGAGACUCGGGUAGGUAGGGAGGUGUGUGCCCAUGGACACACAAAGGCAGAACCUUUCUGGCUUCCAUCAUUAACUGGUUCCAUGAAGCUGAACCUGACCUGCUUGAAGGCCAGGGUUGUCUGCCCCUCCCCUUGGGAGGACCAAGUUGGAUCCCCAAAGAUAAGCCUAAGCAGUCCAUGUUUAGGUUCUGUGCAGCUUACAGGGGCCUCAGAGCUACUGUGGUUUGGAGACAGGGUCAGAUGGUUAGCUUCUUUGAGUUUCUGCUCUUUGUGGAGUACAAAAAUAUGAGGCAGGGUUUGCAAACCUCAACAGUUGGGGCCAGGCAGGUAACAUAGAUAUGUGAAGUGGCUGAGUCUGUAGACCCAUCUAAAGGAAUCCAAAUCAGUCUUUUUUUUUUUCUGAGACAAAUUUCACUCUGUCAUCCAGGCUGGAGUGCAAUGGCGCAAUCUUGGCUCACUGCAACCUCCACCUCCUGGGUUCAAGCAAUUUGACAGCCUCAGCCUCCCGAGUAGCUGGAACUACAGGCACCUGCCACCAUGCCCAGCUGAUUUUUUGUAUUUUUAGUAGAGACGGGGGUUUCGCCUUGUUGGCCAGGCUGCUGUCGAACUCCUGACCUCAGGUGAUCUGCCCACCUUGGCCUCCCAAAGUGCUGGGAUUACAGGCGUGAGCCUCCGCACCCGGCCAAAAAAUCAGUCAUUUAAAAAUAGCUUAUUGGCCCAGCAAAACACUCCUGGGGGCUAGCCUUGGUAAGUUUGUGACUCCUAGUAAGGGGUCAUGGAAACCGAAGCGGGGGCAGGGUGGAACUUGGGUGUAGGCAUUUUUGUGGGCAGGUCUGUGCAGAGAGAGUUUGAGUGCUGGAGAUGUCCAUCCCAGAGCUGAGCUUAAGUGUGGCUGCUGGUUAGGAAGCACUAAUCUGAGAGGCCGAGAGAAAUGGAAUUACACUUGGUCCUGAGGUGUGGACUACUUUCCCGUCUAGAAGCUGAGAGUAUUAGGUGACGCUAGUUCAGGUCAUGCCUUGCCCACAGCACUCUUUACUCAGGGUGAUUCAACUCUGCCCUAGAAUAUAUUUUUAUAUAAAUAUUUACAGAACAAAUCCAGAGAAUCUGUGGGGAGAAAUGGUGGAUUUUGAAUGAGAAGAGUCCUAGGCCUCGUAGAAAUUAAGCUCCCUUUCCUUCUACAGGGAAUUAAAGCCCAAAUCUACAAGCCUUAGACCUUAGCUCUCUUGCAUCUCAUUAAUGCUCCUCCCAAGAAAAAUCUUUGUGCACAUUUUCUCUUUAGGAGAAAGGGGAGGGGCAGACAACCCUGACCUUCAAGUAGGUCAGGUUCAGCUUCAUGGAAUCAGUUAAUGAUGGAAGCCAGGUUCUGCCUUUGUGUGCCCAUGAGUCUCACCACCUACCUGAGUCUCACCACCCAGCACUUCUCUAUUCUCCAGACCUCCUUCCUUCCAGAACCCGAGACUACCGAGACUACAGCCCUGGUCCUAGGAAGUAGGGCUAGGAGAAAUGCAAAAUUGGGGGUUUUGUUAAAGUUACAGACCCAGUCCCCUCCUCCUCUCUUGAAUGCUGCUGAAUGCUAAAUUACACAAGAACUUUGGACAGUAGAGGUUUUUUUUUUUUUAUCCCCAGCAGAUAUUCUGAACCUCAUUUUUUAGUUUUGAGGACAGAGUGUGUUUGCGUAAGUUAGAGCCGUAAGUAGUGCUGGUCCACAUUUCCCCAGCCUGGGCCCUAGGCAGGAGCCACGGCUGCUCAUCCGUCUGGGAUGAGCCUCUAAGACGGUUGAGGAACCUGUGUAUGUUCUAUGUUCAAGAGGCUGCGAUUAAGAGCGUGUCCCCCAGAGUCAGAAAGAACUUUUCAAAACCCGGCACUGUUUCUUCCGGCUGCGUGACCUUGAACCAGUAACUUAAUGUCUUUUUUUUUUUUUUUUUUUUUUGAGGCAGAAUCUCACUCUCUCUCGCAGGCUGGAGUGCAGUGGUGCAAUCUCAGCUCACUGCAGCCUCCACCUCCUGGUUUCAAGUGAUUCUCCUGUCUCAGCCUCCCCGGUAGCUAGGACUACAGUCGUGUGCUACCACGCCCAGCUAAUUUUGUAUUUUUAGUAGAGAUGGAGUUUUACCAUGUUGGCCAGGCUGGUCUCAAACUCCUGACCUCAGGUGAGCCACCCGCCUUGGCCUCCUAAAAGUGCUGGGAUUACAGGUGUGAGCCAAUGCCCCCAGCCAACUUAAUGUCUUUUUUUUUUUUUUUUUUUUUUUUGAGACAGAGUCUCAUUCUGCCGCCCAGGCUGGAGUGCAAUGGCGAGAUCUCGGCUCACUGCAAGCUCCGCCUCCUGGGUUCACGCCAUUCUCCUGCCUCAGCCUCCCGAGUAGCUGGGACUACAGGCACCCACCACCACACCCAGCUAAUUUUUUGUAUUUUUUAGUAGAGACGGGGUUUCACCGUGUUAGCCAGGGAUGGUCUCGAUCUCCUGACCUUGUGAUCCGCCCGCCUUGGCCUCCCAAAGUGCUGGGAUUACAGGCGUGAGACACCGCGCCCAGCCAACUUAAUAUCUUUUGUGCAGCUUCCUCAUCUAUGAAAUGGGGACAACAGUGGGCCCUCACCCCACAGGGAGUUAUGGUGACGUGAUGCAUGUCAAUGGCAGGGAUAUGUCACAGCCGACAUUUAUUGAGUACUUACUAACAUUCUCUGUGGCAAACCAAAGGAAACAAAGCGGAGAGAAGCAUACUGUGUCCUCCUUUGAACUCCUGGGCACUUGCUAAACAGUGUGUCAGUCUUCCUGGCGUAUCAUAACUUUUUCUUAACUCAAGAGCAGAAUCUAGGUCUUUUUUUUUUUCUACUAGUCUCGCUCUAAGGUGCGCCCAGGUUCAAGCAAUAAUCCUGCUUCAGCCUCCUGAGUAGCUGGGAUUACAGGCGCCUGCCACUACGCCCAGCUAAUUUUUUGUAUUUUUAGUAGAGAUAGGGUUUCACCAUGUUGGUCAGGCUGGUCUUGAACUUCUGACCUCAGGUGAUCCACCCACCUCGGCCUCCCAAAGUGCUGUGAUUACAGGCGUGAGCCACCGCGCCCAACAAAUCUGGGUCUUUUUCUCUCAACUUGCCUACAGGGUAUAGUAGGCCAUCUUGGGUUGAUCAUGGGCUCAAAACAGUUUGUAGAAGGAAAGAAUGCCACUUUCUAGUCAUUAUUGCCUGUGGGGCCCCAUAUGUGCUGCCUGCAUUACCCUGGGCUGCACACUGCUGUCUGAAGCACUGAAGCCCAUCACCCCUUUCUUCACCCCGCAAACCCGUCCCUCUCUGGCCCGAAGUCGUUGGAGCCUUUCCUGACCACCGCAUUGCUCUGAGCUGCUGCUGCCUUCCUGCUUCACUUUCUGUGCUUCUGAUGUAUUCCCGUCCCCAGGCUUCCCAGGUGGCUUCCCCUCUUCCCCUGGGGGCUGAUUUCCACUGAGCAGCCAACCGCAGCCUCUGGCCACAAGGAGAGCGGAGCACAGGAGCAGGAAGCCGCCUACCACCAUGAGCAGCACGCUGUCACCCACAGACUUUGACAGCUUGGAAAUCCAGGGCCAGUACAGUGACAUCAACAACCGCUGGGACCUUCCUGACUCGGACUGGGACAAUGACAGCAGCUCGGCCCGCCUCUUUGAGAGGUCUCGCAUUAAGGCUCUGGCAGAUGAACGAGAAGCUGUGCAGAAGAAAACCUUCACCAAGUGGGUAAACUCGCACCUGGCCCGGGUCACGUGCCGGGUGGGGGACCUGUACAGCGACCUCCGGGACGGACGCAACCUGCUGAGGCUCCUCGAGGUGCUCUCGGGAGAGAUACUGCCAAAGCCUACAAAGGGCCGCAUGCGGAUCCACUGCCUGGAGAACGUGGACAAGGCACUGCAGUUCCUCAAGGAGCAGAAAGUGCACUUGGAAAACAUGGGCUCCCAUGACAUUGUGGACGGAAACCACCGACUGACCCUUGGGCUGGUCUGGACCAUCAUCCUUCGAUUCCAGAUCCAAGACAUCAGUGUGGAGACAGAAGACAACAAGGAGAAGAAGUCAGCCAAGGAUGCCCUGCUUCUGUGGUGCCAGAUGAAGACUGCAGGUUAUCCCAACGUCAAUGUACACAACUUCACCACCAGCUGGAGAGAUGGACUAGCUUUCAACGCCAUCGUGCAUAAACACCGGCCAGACCUGCUGGAUUUUGAGUCUCUGAAGAAGUGUAAUGCACACUAUAAUCUGCAGAAUGCAUUCAAUCUGGCUGAAAAGGAACUGGGACUUACCAAGCUGCUGGAUCCCGAAGACGUGAAUGUGGACCAGCCAGAUGAGAAGUCAAUCAUUACCUAUGUGGCUACUUACUACCAUUACUUCUCCAAGAUGAAGGCCCUGGCCGUGGAAGGCAAGAGAAUUGGCAAGGUGCUGGACCAUGCCAUGGAGGCAGAGCGCCUGGUGGAGAAAUACGAGUCCCUGGCCUCGGAGCUGCUGCAGUGGAUCGAGCAAACGAUCGUGACCCUCAAUGACCGGCAGUUGGCCAACUCCCUUAGCGGGGUCCAGAACCAGCUGCAGUCCUUCAACUCCUACCGCACCGUGGAGAAGCCGCCCAAGUUUACCGAGAAAGGGAACUUGGAAGUGCUGCUCUUCACCAUCCAGAGCAAGCUUCGGGCCAACAACCAGAAGGUCUACACGCCCCGCGAGGGCCGGCUCAUCUCGGACAUCAACAAGGCUUGGGAGCGGCUGGAGAAGGCGGAGCACGAGCGUGAGCUGGCCCUGCGCACCGAGCUCAUCCGCCAGGAGAAGCUGGAGCAGCUGGCCGCCCGCUUCGACCGCAAGGCUGCCAUGCGGGAGACCUGGCUCAGCGAGAACCAGCGCCUCGUGUCCCAGGACAACUUUGGGCUGGAGCUGGCAGCUGUCGAGGCAGCAGUACGGAAGCACGAAGCCAUUGAGACGGACAUCGUGGCCUACAGCGGCCGGGUGCAGGCAGUGGACGCCGUGGCUGCAGAGCUGGCCGCCGAGCGCUACCACGACAUCAAGCGCAUCGCCGCUCGGCAGCACAACGUGGCACGGCUCUGGGACUUCUUGCGGCAGAUGGUGGCCGCCCGGCGGGAGCGGCUCCUCCUCAACCUGGAGCUGCAGAAGGUGUUCCAGGACCUGCUCUACCUCAUGGACUGGAUGGAAGAGAUGAAGGGCCGGCUGCAGUCUCAGGACCUGGGCAGGCACCUAGCAGGAGUGGAGGACCUGCUGCAGCUGCACGAGCUGGUGGAGGCAGACAUCGCCGUGCAGGCCGAGAGGGUGCGGGCCGUCAGCGCCUCUGCCCUGCGCUUCUGCAACCCAGGGAAAGAGUAUAGACCUUGCGACCCGCAGCUGGUGUCGGAGCGGGUGGCCAAGCUAGAGCAGAGCUAUGAGGCACUGUGCGAGUUGGCAGCGGCGCGGCGGGCCCGGCUGGAGGAAUCACGGCGGCUCUGGCGUUUCCUCUGGGAGGUGGGUGAAGCUGAGGCCUGGGUGCGGGAGCAGCAGCACCUCCUGGCCUCAGCCGACACGGGCCGAGACCUGACCGGUGCCCUCCGCCUGCUCAACAAGCACACAGCCCUGCGGGGCGAGAUGAGCGGCCGGCUGGGGCCCCUGAAGCUCACCCUGGAGCAGGGCCAGCAGUUGGUGGCCGAGGGUCACCCUGGGGCAAGCCAGGCCUCUGCCCGUGCAGCUGAACUCCAAGCCCAGUGGGAGCGGCUAGAGGCCCUGGCCGAGGAGCGUGCCCAGCGGCUGGCCCAAGCCGCCAGCCUCUACCAGUUCCAGGCCGAUGCAAACGACAUGGAGGCCUGGUUGGUUGACGCACUGCGCCUGGUGUCCAGCCCCGAGCUGGGGCACGACGAGUUCUCCACGCAGGCUCUAGCCAGGCAGCAUCGGGCCCUGGAGGAGGAGAUUCGAAGCCACCGGCCAACCCUGGACGCCUUGAGGGAACAGGCAGCAGCCCUGCCCCCCACACUGAGCCGCACGCCCGAGGUGCAGAGCCGGGUGCCCACCCUGGAGCGGCACUACGAGGAGCUGCAGGCCCGGGCAGGCGAGCGAGCGCGGGCCUUGGAGGCAGCCCUGGCGCUCUACACCAUGCUCAGCGAGGCCGGGGCCUGUGGACUCUGGGUGGAGGAGAAGGAGCAGUGGCUCAACGGGCUGGCCCUGCCUGAACGCCUGGAGGACCUGGAGGUCGUGCAGCAGAGGUUCGAGACCCUGGAGCCUGAAAUGAACACCCUUGCAGCACAAAUCACCGCGGUGAAUGACAUUGCCGAGCAGUUACUGAAGGCCAACCCCCCAGGCAAAGACCGCAUUGUCAACACCCAGGAGCAGCUCAACCACAGGUGGCAGCAGUUUCGGCGUCUGGCAGACGGCAAGAAGGCAGCUCUCACCUCAGCCCUGAGCAUCCAGAACUACCACUUAGAGUGCACGGAGACCCAGGCCUGGAUGAGAGAGAAGACCAAAGUCAUCGAGUCCACCCAGGGCCUAGGCAACGAUCUGGCUGGGGUGCUGGCCCUGCAGCGCAAGCUGGCCGGCACGGAGCGGGACCUGGAGGCCAUCGCCGCCCGGGUGGGCGAACUGACUCGAGAGGCAAAUGCCCUGGCUGCCGGCCAUCCCGCUCAGGCAGUGGCCAUCAACGCCCGGCUGAGAGAGGUGCAGACCGGCUGGGAGGACCUCAGGGCCACCAUGCGGCGUCGAGAAGAGUCGCUGGGGGAGGCGCGGCGGCUGCAGGACUUCUUGCGCAGCUUGGAUGACUUCCAGGCCUGGCUAGGCCGCACUCAGACUGCUGUGGCCUCUGAAGAAGGGCCGGCCACCCUGCCUGAGGCAGAGGCCCUCCUGGCCCAACAUGCAGCCCUGCGGGGAGAGGUGGAGCGGGCCCAGAGCGAGUAUAGCCGGCUGCGAGCCCUGGGCGAGGAGGUGACCCGGGACCAGGCUGACCCCCAGUGCCUCUUCCUACGACAGCGACUGGAGGCCCUGGGAACUGGCUGGGAGGAGCUGGGCCGAAUGUGGGAGAGCCGGCAAGGUCGCCUGGCCCAGGCCCACGGCUUCCAGGGAUUCCUGCGGGAUGCUCGUCAGGCUGAGGGCGUGCUCAGCAGCCAGGAAUAUGUUCUGUCUCACACGGAGAUGCCAGGGACACUCCAGGCUGCUGAUGCUGCCAUUAAAAAACUGGAGGACUUCAUGAGCACCAUGGACGCCAAUGGGGAACGGAUCCACGGGCUCCUGGAGGCUGGCCGCCAGCUGGUAUCUGAAGGCAACAUCCACGCCGACAAGAUUCGGGAAAAGGCAGACUCCAUUGAGAGGAGGCACAAGAAGAAUCAAGACGCAGCGCAGCAAUUUCUGGGCCGUCUUCGGGACAACCGGGAGCAGCAGCAUUUCCUGCAAGAUUGUCACGAGCUGAAGCUCUGGAUCGACGAGAAGAUGCUGACAGCCCAGGACGUGUCCUAUGACGAGGCCCGCAACCUGCAUACUAAGUGGCAGAAGCACCAGGCAUUCAUGGCCGAGCUGGCUGCCAACAAAGACUGGCUGGACAAGGUGGACAAGGAAGGGCGAGAGCUCACCCUUGAGAAGCCAGAGCUGAAAGCCCUGGUGUCGGAGAAGCUGAGAGACCUGCACAGGCGCUGGGACGAGCUGGAGACCACCACCCAAGCCAAGGCCCGCAGCCUCUUUGAUGCCAACCGAGCUGAGCUGUUUGCCCAGAGCUGCUGUGCCCUGGAGAGCUGGCUGGAGAGCCUGCAGGCCCAGCUGCACUCGGAUGACUACGGCAAGGACCUCACCAGCGUCAACAUCCUGCUCAAGAAGCAGCAGAUGCUGGAAUGGGAGAUGGCUGUGAGAGAGAAGGAGGUGGAGGCAAUCCAGGCCCAGGCCAAAGCACUGGCCCAGGAGGACCAGGGUGCAGGGGAGGUGGAGAGAACCUCGAGGGCCGUGGAGGAGAAGUUCAGGGCCUUGUGCCAGCCCAUGCGGGAACGCUGCCGGCGCCUGCAGGCUUCUCGCGAGCAGCACCAGUUCCACCGCGAUGUGGAAGAUGAGAUUUUGUGGGUGACAGAGCGGCUGCCCAUGGCCAGCUCCAUGGAGCAUGGCAAGGACCUGCCCAGCGUCCAGCUUCUCAUGAAGAAAAACCAGACCCUGCAGAAAGAGAUUCAGGGCCAUGAGCCCCGGAUCGCGGACCUGAGGGAGCGGCAGCGUGCUCUAGGUGCAGCAGCAGCAGGUCCAGAGCUGGCUGAGCUGCAGGAAAUGUGGAAACGCCUGGGCCACGAGCUGGAACUUCGAGGGAAGCGACUGGAGGAUGCCCUGCGAGCCCAGCAGUUCUACCGCGAUGCCGCCGAGGCGGAGGCCUGGAUGGGCGAGCAGGAAUUACACAUGAUGGGCCAGGAGAAGGCCAAGGAUGAGCUGAGUGCCCAGGCAGAGGUGAAGAAGCACCAGGUGCUGGAGCAAGCCCUGGCCGACUACGCGCAGACCAUCCACCAGCUGGCGGCCAGCAGCCAGGACAUGAUUGACCACGAGCACCCAGAGAGCACUCGGAUAUCCAUCCGCCAAGCCCAGGUGGACAAGCUGUAUGCCGGCCUGAAGGAGCUGGCUGGAGAGCGGCGGGAGCGCCUGCAGGAGCACCUCCGGCUGUGCCAGCUCCGCCGCGAGCUGGAUGACCUGGAACAGUGGAUCCAGGAGCGCGAGGUGGUGGCGGCCUCCCACGAGCUGGGCCAGGACUACGAGCAUGUGACUAUGCUCCGAGACAAAUUCCGAGAGUUCUCCCGGGACACAAGCACCAUCGGUCAGGAGCGCGUAGAUAGCGCCAAUGCGCUGGCCAAUGGGCUCAUUGCUGGGGGCCAUGCUGCACGGGCCACCGUGGCCGAGUGGAAGGACAGUCUCAACGAGGCCUGGGCUGACCUGCUUGAGCUGCUGGACACACGGGGUCAGGUGCUGGCCGCGGCGUACGAGCUGCAGCGCUUCCUGCACGGGGCACGCCAAGCCCUGGCGCGGGUGCAGCACAAGCAGCAGCAGCUUCCGGACGGGACUGGCCGCGACCUCAACGCUGCCGAGGCCCUGCAGCGCCGACACUGUGCCUACGAGCAUGACAUUCAGGCCCUCAGCCCCCAGGUCCAGCAGGUGCAGGACGACGGCCACCGGCUCCAGAAGGCCUACGCUGGAGACAAGGCUGAGGAGAUCGGCCGCCACAUGCAGGCCGUGGCCGAGGCCUGGGCCCAGCUUCAGGGAAGCUCUGCCGCCCGCCGGCAGCUGCUGCUGGACACCACAGACAAGUUCCGCUUCUUCAAGGCUGUCCGGGAACUGAUGCUCUGGAUGGAUGAGGUCAACCUGCAGAUGGAUGCCCAGGAGCGUCCCCGGGAUGUGUCCUCCGCGGAUCUAGUCAUCAAGAACCAGCAAGGCAUCAAGGCAGAGAUAGAGGCCCGGGCAGACCGCUUCUCCUCCUGCAUCGACAUGGGGAAGGAGCUGCUGGCCAGGAGCCACUAUGCGGCCGAGGAGAUCUCAGAGAAGCUGUCUCAGCUGCAGGCACGGCGCCAGGAGACAGCUGAGAAGUGGCAGGAGAAGAUGGACUGGCUUCAGCUGGUUUUGGAGGUGCUUGUGUUUGGAAGAGAUGCAGGGAUGGCAGAGGCCUGGCUCUGCAGCCAGGAGCCACUGGUGCGCAGCGCUGAGCUGGGUUGCACGGUCGACGAAGUUGAGAGCCUCAUCAAGCGGCACGAGGCCUUCCAGAAGUCAGCAGUGGCCUGGGAGGAGCGAUUCUGUGCGCUGGAGAAGCUUACUGCGCUAGAGGAGCGGGAGAAGGAGCGAAAGAGAAAGAGGGAGGAGGAGGAGCGGCGGAAACAGCCGCCUGCUCCCGAACCCACAGCCAGUGUGCCUCCAGGGGACCUGGUGGGCGGCCAGACAGCUUCUGACACCACCUGGGACGGAACCCAGCCACGGCCACCACCAUCCACACAAGCACCCAGUGUUAAUGGAGUCUGCACAGAUGGAGAGCCCUCACAGCCCCUGCUGGGACAACAGAGACUUGAGCACAGCAGCUUCCCCGAAGGGCCGGGACCUGGCUCAGGGGACGAAGCCAAUGGGCCCCGGGGAGAGAGGCAGACCCGGACUCGGGGCCCGGCCCCAUCUGCAAUGCCCCAGAGCAGGUCUACCGAGUCAGCCCAUGCUGCCACCCUGCCGCCUCGAGGCCCAGAGCCAUCUGCCCAGGAGCAGAUGGAGGGGAUGCUGUGCCGCAAGCAGGAGAUGGAGGCCUUCGGGAAGAAGGCUGCCAACAGGUCCUGGCAGAACGUGUACUGUGUCCUGCGGCGUGGGAGCCUCGGCUUUUACAAGGAUGCCAAGGCAGCCAGCGCGGGAGUGCCAUACCACGGAGAAGUGCCUGUCAGCCUGGCCAGGGCCCAGGGCAGCGUCGCCUUUGAUUACCGAAAGCGCAAACAUGUCUUCAAGCUGGGCUUACAGGAUGGAAAAGAAUAUUUAUUCCAGGCCAAGGAUGAGGCAGAGAUGAGCUCGUGGCUACGGGUGGUGAAUGCAGCCAUUGCCACAGCGUCUUCUGCCUCUGGAGAGCCUGAAGAGCCGGUGGUGCCCAGCACCACCCGGGGCAUGACCCGGGCCAUGACCAUGCCCCCAGUGUCACCCGUCGGGGCUGAGGGGCCUGUUGUGCUCCGCAGCAAAGACGGCAGAGAACGAGAGCGAGAAAAACGCUUCAGCUUCUUUAAGAAGAACAAGUAGUUGGGGGCAAGGUCCCAGGCCAACUCCCUCCCUCCGUUCAGGAAACUGCCAGGGACAGUCGACAGGGACCGCCCUCUUGUCAGGACAACUGCCUGCUGCUAGGGUCUGUUGCCAAGGUCAACCCAUCACCAGGAACUGUCACUGGGGACGAGUCCAUGUUCCCAAGGGCAGCCCUUCUCUUCUGCUGUUUAAUUCCAGACUGGUGGUGGGACCCAGGUAACCCCCUCUCCCACCCCCGCCGACUUCUCCCCUUUCCCCAGCCUCGUGCCUCUGUCCCUCACCACGGUGUGGACAGUGCCGCACCCUCAACAUAGGCCAUGUGGGGAGUGGCUGCCCCUGCCUCAGGGUCAUUCUCCUGCCAUGCGAGGGCACUCGCCUUCUGCCUUCUGGUUCCUCACCCCUCAGACCAGCCAGGAACCUCUCAGAGCUGAAGCAGGCCCUGGGGGCAGAAGUGCCAGAUGACAGUCAGAGGCGCAGGAGCCCUCCCUCCCCACCCCCACCCUGUAACUCCAGCUGCCACUCCAUCUCCAGCUGCUCUCAAUGGCUUCCAGGUGUGUUGUUCGGGGACAGCCACCGCCUUGAGUCUGGCCAAGGAGGUGAUUAAACAGCUCAGCUUCUCUCACCGCCUCUGGGUGUCUUUGCUUUCCUGACCACAGCCUCUCUGCCCAAGCCUGUGUCCUCUCCUUCCGUUCUGGUCUCCUUCAUCUCACGUUUCCCCAGCCUCCAAGCUCUUGAAGAGCCGUGUCACACUGAGAGCUUCCCUGACCUGGUCUCAUUUCCCUCUGACAGUGACCUCCAGUGUGCUGGGUUGACCAAUGCCAAGCCUCUUUUUAAACCAAAGUAGUUCACCAUGGGUUGGGAUGAUGUCAACAAGCAGUAUUCAUGUUAAAAAGCAAUGAGGGACUCCUUCCCUGGUGCACAAUUUUCUUCACUUGUGAUCUCUAAACUGUUUUCAAAUUGGAAGACUGGGAAGCAUUGCUACAGCCCCAGCCAGUCUCAGCCACUGCUCAGCCCAGUGGUGGAAAGCUGAGCACACAGCGGGUGCUUACUGCCCCCACUUGCCGUCUGCUCUCCAGUAGAUCAAGGGACCUCAGACAGGGAUCUGAGAAGUGGCAGGUUCCAAUAAACUGAUCAACAGAAUGAAGUCACUCUGGGAAGCCAUGAGGUGACUUUACAGCCCAAGCAUGUAAAUAUACACACAGAGGAUAAUAUAUAUUCUUUUUUUUUUUUUUUUUUGAGACAGAGUCUCACUCUGUCAGCCAAGCUGGACUGCAGUGGCGCAAUCACAGCCCAUUGCAACCUCCACCUCCUGGGUUCAAGCAAUCCUCCCACCUCAGCCUCCCGAGUAGCCUGAACCACAGGCACAUGCCAUCAUACCCGACUAAGUCUGUUUGUUUUUUGUAGAGACGGGGUCUCACUAUGUUGCCCAGGUCGGUCUCGAAUUCCUGGGCCCAAGUGAUUCUCUCACCUUGGCCUCAAACUGUUGGGAUUACAGGCGUGAGCCACCAUGCCCAGCUGAGACUACCUUCUGGAUCUGAUGAAGUAUUAGAAAGGAGCGGGUGGCUUCUCCUUUGUCUCUGGUUUGGCAAUCGGAGCUUUCAGGGCACAGUGUUUGUCUCCAGAUGUUGAUGGAAGUGGGCACUCCUUGGUGGCCUCCAACAGGAAAAGCGUGUUCUUUCAUUGUUUCCUAUACACACAGACAACCGUUUUUCCAGGAAGGCAGCCCCAUCUUUAGUCAUUGACUGCGGGCCUAUCAUCAGUCAUGACGAAGACCGAGUUAGGUGUGUGCAGGCCCAGAACUAGCACAUCACAGCCCCAGAGUGGGCUCCAAACCGGUAGACCAGAGAGCCUGCAGGAUAAUUUCCCCCUUAAGAUGGGUAGAUUUACUGUUCCACAGCCAACAGGUGGAUACGCGUAACUAGAACAAUCUGUCAUGGGACUAAGUGGAAGAAUCCAUCAGCACUACACAGCAUCUUUUCUUCAAAUACAACUGUAAAAUCUCCACUGAAGAGACAGUCAUACCUUGGGGGUGCUCAGGGAAUCUAGGUAUUUGCACUCCAAGCUGGCAAGCCUGGGGGCACUGAAGGGAAACAAUAAUUGGAAAUGUCAGAAGGAAAUGUAUAUGGAGAAAUUAAUAGAGAAAUGAUUAUUUUAACACGACACGUAAGUGUAAAUAGGACAGCCAAUUGAAGCAGUCCUGCAGUAGGGGCAGGCAUUGUCAACGGAGAGGUGAGACUGAAGACCCCGAGCAGCAUCUGCAUAUGCGGCAGCAGGACUUCAGGGCAUGAUUCCUUAAGAACAGGACAUAGAAGAGGGGAAGCAUAGUGUCAGGAAUUAAGUCAGAAAACACCUUCAGCUGUGAGUGGAAGAAAGAAAAAAUUCCAGGAAAGACAACAGGAUGGAAUGGGGCGGUGAGGGCUAUGAGACAAGUUAGACACAAAAAUACAAUAAAUGCAGGCAGCACAAAUCAAUGGAGAGAGAUGGCAGAUAAAAAUGGAUUACUUGGGCCGGGCGCGGUGGCUCACGCCUGUAAUCCCAGCACUUUGGGAGGCCGAGGCGGGCGGAUCACGAGGUCAGGAGAUCGAGACCAUCCCGGCUAAAACGGUGAAACCCCGUCUCUACUAAAAAUACAAAAAUUAGCCGGGCGUAGUGGCGGGCGCCUGUAGUCCCAGCUACUUGGGAGGCUGAGGCAGGAGAAUGGCGUGAACCCGGGAGGCGGAGCUUGCAGUGAGCCGAGAUGCCGCCACUGCGCUCCAGCCUGGGUGACAGAGCGAGACUCCAUCUCAAAAAAAAAAAAAAAAAAAAAAUGGAUUACUUGGCCAGGCAUGGUGGUUCACGCUUAUAAUCCCAGCACUUUGGGAAGCCGAGGUGAGUGGGUCACUUGAGCUCAGGAGUUCAAGACCAGCCUGGGCAACAUGGUGAAACCCCAUCUCUACAAAAAUUAGCCAGGUGUAGUGGCAUGUGCCUGUAGUCUCAGCUACUUGGGAGGCUGAGGCAGGAGCAUUGCUUGAACCUGGGAAGCAGAGGUUACAGUGAGCCGAGAUCAUGCCACUGCACUCCAGUCUAGGCAAUAAAGUGAGACCCUGUCUCAAAAAAAAAAAAAUAGGAUUAUGUAGAGAAAAAUAUAUUUGCAUUCUUAACAUCACCUACAAGAGUGGACUUUAGGUCCAUGCUGUCCACAGCAGCAGCCACCCAGCCAUGUGUGGCUACUGAGAUGUAGCCAAACCAAGUGUGUCAUGACUCUGAAACACCAGGUAUGAAGCAUGGAAGAGGACAACAACUUUAAAUACCUUAAUUUUUAUAUUGAUUAUGUGUUGAAAUAAUAUUUUAGAUAUAUUGGGUUUCAAAAGUAUCAUUAAAGUGAAUUUCAACUA